AGAAUCGUUUUGGGUCUGGUCGCCAAGAUGGCGUCCUCCGCCUCCGCCCGGACUCCGGCAGGGAAGCGAGUGAUAAAUCAGGAAGAAUUGCGGCGGUUAAUGAAGGAGAAGCAGCGUCUGAGCACCAGUCGGAAACGGAUAGAAUCUCCAUUCGCGAAGUACAACCGUUUGGGGCAGCUGAGUUGUGCCCUGUGUAACACUCCGGUUAAGAGCGAGCUCCUGUGGCAGACUCACGUCCUGGGAAAGCAGCACCGAGAGAAAGUGGCCGAGCUGAAAGGCGCGAAGGAAGCCAGCCAGGGUUCGUCCGCCAGUUCAGCGCCUCAUUCCGUCAAGAGGAAAGCGCCGGACGCAGACGACCAAGAUGUCAAGAGAGCGAAGGCCACCUUGGUGCCUCAGGUACAGCCCUCCACAUCUGCGUGGACCACCAACUUUGACAAAAUAGGAAAGGAGUUCAUUAGAGCGACUCCCAGUAAGCCUUCAGGACUCAGUUUACUCCCCGAUUAUGAAGAUGAGGAGGAGGAGGAAGAGGAGGAGGAAGGAGAUGGAGAAAGAAAAAGGGGGGACGCCAGCAAGCCGCUCUCCGACGCACAGGGCAAGGAGCACUCAGUUUCCUCUUCACGGGAGGUAACAAGUAGUGUGCUGCCAAACGAUUUCUUUAGUACUAAUCCUCCCAAGGCCCCCAUAAUUCCUCAUUCAGGGUCAAUUGAGAAAGCAGAAAUACAUGAAAAAGUGGUGGAAAGGAGAGAAAACACCGCGGAAGCGUUACCGGAAGGUUUUUUUGACGACCCUGAGGUAGAUGCAAGAGUACGAAAGGUUGAUGCUCCAAAAGAUCAGAUGGACAAAGAGUGGGACGAAUUCCAAAAAGCCAUGAGGCAGGUCAACACUAUUUCCGAAGCCAUAGUUGCCGAAGAGGAUGAGGAGGGACGGUUGGACCGCCAGAUUGGGGAGAUCGAUGAGCAGAUAGAGUGUUACCGACGGGUGGAAAAGCUACGGAAUCGCCAGGAUGAAAUAAAAAAUAAACUUAAAGAAAUCCUGACCAUAAAAGAACUGCAGAAAAAGGAAGAAGAGAAUGCUGACAGCGAUGAUGAGGGGGAACUACAGGAUUUGUUGUCUCAGGAUUGGAGGGUGAAAGGGGCAUUGUUAUAGGGUUUUAAAGACCCAAGGUUUCUAACAGCCUCUGCUGUUGUAUAAAAAGUGCUGUCUCUCAGUAGUAUAGCGGUUACUUCAUGCCUCAAGAUUUGGGUACCUGGAUUGCUAAACUGGAUUGUUGAGAUAAAAUGAGCCAGUGAGCUACAGCACUUUGGAAAAUUUGUGUAACAUGUUUUUGAGGUAAAGUUGUUUUUGAAAUUUCUGAAGUGUUAUAUACCAAAAUGCCAACAUUUCCACGACAGACUUAACUGUAUAAUUUCGUUGUAAAAUCUGUAAGUUGUAAAUAUUGUACAUAGUUAAAUCUGUAUUCUGUUUUGAAUUUUUUUAAUUAAUAGAAAGACCAACCGGCAAACUUUCAGAUGAAUGCUUACUGUGGUAUUUGGAAUGUAUGUAUCUUCUGAACCCUACAUCAAGUUGAAAAGGUUUGUUUUCUUGUUUCUUUGGUUUUUGUAUGGUUUUUUAGAACACUUCAUAAACACAUAAGUCAUUGUAGGUUAAUCAGUUCUCUUAGUGUGCUUUAUUUUAAAAACAUAAGAAAACUAUAUGCCAAACAUGACCAAACCAAUGAUGGUCAGAUGUGGUUGCACAUGAGAGUCACCUAUGAAGCAUUAAAAUAAUUAAAGUGUCUGAGGCCUUCCCCUUCAAUAAAUCUGGGAUUGGGCCCAGGCAACUGUGUUUUUUAAGCACCCAGGUUAUUCUAAUAUAUGCCAGGGUUAGAGAGUAACUGCCCUAAAUCCAGAACCCAUUUAUGUUUUUCAGGUUUUUUCUUUUUCUUUAAAUAACACAUUCCAUAAAUUUGCUGUUUCUUGAAUGAAGGAAAAAAUAUUAUCUUUUAUUUAUUUCAUCCAGCCUUAAAUUUUGUUAUUUGGUGGUAAAUUAGGGUUCCUUGUUUGCAGGUCCUAUCUAUUGUAGAAAGAAUAUUUAAGUUGUCUUUCCAGCAGUAACAAUUGGCUCUUGCUGGUCAUUGAUAGUUUAAAUCACUCCUUCCUUUAGAGAUUGAGGUACUCAAAUAGGAAAAGGGAAUUAGCAGUGUUCUGGAGUUGAAAUGCAUACAGCAUAUUCAAAUAAAAGUGAGCAAUAAUAAUAAUA